AGUGCUGGCUGGACAGCUGCUCUGGGCAGGAGAGAGAGGGAGAGACAAGAGACACACACAGAGAGACGGCGAGGAAGGGAAAGACCCAGAGGGACGCCUAGAACGAGACUUGGAGCCAGACAGAGGAAGAGGGGACGUGUGUUUGCAGACUGGCUGGGCCCGUGACCCAGCUUCCUGAGUCCUCCGUGCAGGUGGCAGCUGUACCAGGCUGGCAGGUCACUGAGAGUGGGCAGCUGGGCCCCAGAACUGUGCCUGGCCCAGUGGGCAGCAGGAGCUCCUGACUUGGGACCAUGGUGAUUCUUCAGCAGGGGGACCAUGUGUGGAUGGACCUGAGAUUGGGGCAGGAGUUCGACGUGCCCAUCGGGGCGGUGGUGAAGCUCUGCGACUCUGGGCAGGUCCAGGUGGUGGAUGAUGAAGACAAUGAACACUGGAUCUCUCCGCAGAACGCAACGCACAUCAAGCCUAUGCACCCCACGUCGGUCCACGGCGUGGAGGACAUGAUCCGCCUGGGGGACCUCAACGAGGCGGGCAUCUUGCGCAACCUGCUUAUCCGCUACCGGGACCACCUCAUCUACACGUAUACGGGCUCCAUCCUGGUGGCUGUGAACCCCUACCAGCUGCUCUCCAUCUACUCGCCAGAGCACAUCCGCCAGUAUACCAACAAGAAGAUUGGGGAGAUGCCCCCCCACAUCUUUGCCAUUGCUGACAACUGCUACUUCAACAUGAAACGCAACAGCCGAGACCAGUGCUGCAUCAUCAGUGGGGAAUCUGGGGCCGGGAAGACGGAGAGCACAAAGCUGAUCCUGCAGUUCCUGGCAGCCAUCAGUGGGCAGCACUCGUGGAUUGAGCAGCAGGUCUUGGAGGCCACCCCCAUUCUGGAAGCAUUUGGGAAUGCCAAGACCAUCCGCAAUGACAACUCAAGCCGUUUCGGAAAGUACAUCGACAUCCACUUCAACAAGCGGGGCGCCAUCGAGGGCGCGAAGAUUGAGCAGUACCUGCUGGAAAAGUCACGUGUCUGUCGCCAGGCCCUGGAUGAAAGGAACUACCACGUGUUCUACUGCAUGCUGGAGGGUAUGAGUGAGGAUCAGAAGAAGAAGCUGGGCUUGGGCCAGGCCUCUGACUACAACUACUUGGCCAUGGGUAACUGCAUAACCUGUGAGGGCCGGGUGGACAGCCAGGAGUACGCCAACAUCCGCUCCGCCAUGAAGGUGCUCAUGUUCACUGACACCGAGAACUGGGAGAUCUCGAAGCUCCUGGCUGCCAUCCUGCACCUGGGCAACCUGCAGUAUGAGGCACGCACAUUUGAAAACCUGGAUGCCUGUGAGGUUCUCUUCUCCCCAUCGCUGGCCACAGCUGCAUCCCUGCUUGAGGUGAACCCCCCAGACCUGAUGAGCUGCCUGACUAGCCGCACCCUCAUCACCCGCGGGGAGACGGUGUCCACCCCACUGAGCAGGGAACAGGCACUGGACGUGCGCGACGCCUUCGUAAAGGGGAUCUACGGGCGGCUGUUCGUGUGGAUUGUGGACAAGAUCAACGCAGCAAUUUACAAGCCUCCCUCCCAGGAUGUGAAGAACUCUCGCAGGUCCAUCGGCCUCCUGGACAUCUUUGGGUUUGAGAACUUUGCUGUGAACAGCUUUGAGCAGCUCUGCAUCAACUUCGCCAAUGAGCACCUGCAGCAGUUCUUUGUGCGGCACGUGUUCAAGCUGGAGCAGGAGGAAUAUGACCUGGAGAGCAUUGACUGGCUGCACAUCGAGUUCACUGACAACCAGGAUGCCCUGGACAUGAUUGCCAACAAGCCCAUGAACAUCAUCUCCCUCAUCGAUGAGGAGAGCAAGUUCCCCAAGGGCACAGACACCACCAUGUUACACAAGCUGAACUCCCAGCACAAGCUCAACGCCAACUACAUCCCCCCCAAGAACAACCAUGAGACCCAGUUUGGCAUCAACCAUUUUGCAGGCAUCGUCUACUAUGAGACCCAAGGCUUCCUGGAGAAGAACCGAGACACCCUGCAUGGGGACAUUAUCCAGCUGGUCCACUCCUCCAGGAACAAGUUCAUCAAGCAGAUCUUCCAGGCCGAUGUCGCCAUGGGCGCCGAGACCAGGAAGCGCUCGCCCACACUUAGCAGCCAGUUCAAGCGGUCACUGGAGCUGCUGAUGCGCACGCUGGGUGCCUGCCAGCCCUUCUUUGUGCGAUGCAUCAAGCCCAAUGAGUUCAAGAAGCCCAUGCUGUUCGACCGGCACCUGUGCGUGCGCCAGCUGCGGUACUCAGGAAUGAUGGAGACCAUCCGAAUCCGCCGAGCUGGCUACCCCAUCCGCUACAGCUUCGUAGAGUUUGUGGAGCGGUACCGUGUGCUGCUGCCAGGUGUGAAGCCGGCCUACAAGCAGGGCGACCUCCGCGGGACUUGCCAGCGCAUGGCUGAGGCUGUGCUGGGCACCCACGAUGACUGGCAGAUAGGCAAAACCAAGAUCUUUCUGAAGGACCACCAUGACAUGCUGCUGGAAGUGGAGCGGGACAAAGCCAUCACCGACAGAGUCAUCCUCCUUCAGAAAGUCAUCCGGGGAUUCAAAGACAGGUCUAACUUUCUGAAGCUGAAGAACGCUGCCACACUGAUCCAGAGGCACUGGCGGGGUCACAACUGUAGGAAGAACUACGGGCUGAUGCGUCUGGGCUUCCUGCGGCUGCAGGCCCUGCACCGCUCCCGGAAGCUGCACCAGCAGUACCGCCUGGCCCGCCAGCGCAUCAUCCAGUUCCAGGCCCGCUGCCGCGCCUAUCUGGUGCGCAAGGCCUUCCGCCACCGCCUCUGGGCUGUGCUCACCGUGCAGGCCUAUGCCCGGGGCAUGAUCGCCCGCAGGCUGCACCAACGCCUCAGGGCUGAGUAUCUGUGGCGCCUCGAGGCUGAGAAAAUGCGGCUGGCGGAGGAAGAGAAGCUUCGGAAGGAGAUGAGCGCCAAGAAGGCCAAGGAGGAGGCCGAGCGCAAGCAUCAGGAGCGCCUGGCCCAGCUGGCUCGUGAGGACGCUGAGCGGGAGCUGAAGGAGAAGGAGGCCGCUCGGCGGAAGAAGGAGCUCCUGGAGCAGAUGGAAAGGGCCCGCCAUGAGCCUGUCAAUCACUCAGACAUGGUGGACAAGAUGUUUGGCUUCCUGGGGACUUCAGGUGGCCUGCCAGGCCAGGAGGGCCAGGCACCUAGUGGCUUUGAGGACCUGGAGCGAGGGCGGAGGGAGAUGGUGGAGGAGGACCUGGAUGCAGCCCUGCCCCUGCCUGACGAGGAUGAGGAGGACCUCUCUGAGUAUAAAUUUGCCAAGUUCGCGGCCACCUACUUCCAGGGGACAACCACGCACUCCUACACCCGGCGGCCACUCAAACAGCCACUGCUCUACCAUGACGACGAGGGUGACCAGCUGGCAGCCCUGGCGGUCUGGAUCACCAUCCUCCGCUUCAUGGGGGACCUCCCUGAGCCCAAGUACCACACAGCCAUGAGUGAUGGCAGUGAGAAGAUCCCUGUGAUGACCAAGAUUUAUGAGACCCUGGGCAAGAAGACGUACAAGAGGGAGCUGCAGGCCCUGCAGGGCGAGGGCGAGGCCCAGCUCCCCGAGGGCCAGAAGAAGAGCAGUGUGAGGCACAAGCUGGUGCAUUUGACUCUGAAAAAGAAGUCCAAGCUCACAGAGGAGGUGACCAAGAGGCUGCAUGACGGGGAGUCCACAGUGCAGGGCAACAGCAUGCUGGAGGACCGGCCCACCUCCAACCUGGAGAAGCUGCACUUCAUCAUCGGCAAUGGCAUCCUGCGGCCAGCACUCCGGGACGAGAUCUACUGCCAGAUCAGCAAGCAGCUGACCCACAACCCCUCCAAGAGCAGCUAUGCCCGGGGCUGGAUUCUCGUGUCUCUCUGCGUGGGCUGUUUCGCCCCCUCCGAGAAGUUUGUCAAGUACCUGCGGAACUUCAUCCACGGGGGCCCGCCCGGCUACGCCCCGUACUGUGAGGAGCGCCUGAGAAGGACCUUUGUCAAUGGGACACGGACACAGCCGCCCAGCUGGCUGGAGCUGCAGGCCACCAAGUCCAAGAAGCCAAUCAUGUUGCCCGUGACAUUCAUGGAUGGGACCACCAAGACCCUGCUGACGGACUCGGCAACCACGGCCAAGGAGCUCUGCAACGCGCUGGCCGACAAGAUCUCUCUCAAGGACCGGUUCGGGUUCUCCCUCUACAUUGCCCUGUUUGACAAGGUGUCCUCCCUGGGCAGCGGCAGUGACCACGUCAUGGACGCCAUCUCCCAGUGCGAGCAGUACGCCAAGGAGCAGGGCGCCCAGGAGCGCAACGCCCCCUGGAGGCUCUUCUUCCGCAAAGAGGUCUUCACGCCCUGGCACAGCCCCUCCGAGGACAACGUGGCCACCAACCUCAUCUACCAGCAGGUGGUGCGAGGAGUCAAGUUUGGGGAGUACAGGUGUGAGAAGGAGGACGACCUGGCUGAGCUGGCCUCCCAGCAGUACUUUGUAGACUAUGGCUCUGAGAUGAUCCUGGAGCGCCUCCUGAACCUCGUGCCCACCUACAUCCCCGACCGCGAGAUCACGCCCCUGAAGACGCUGGAGAAGUGGGCCCAGCUGGCCAUCGCCGCCCACAAGAAGGGGAUUUAUGCCCAGAGGAGAACUGAUGCCCAGAAGGUCAAAGAGGAUGUGGUCAGUUAUGCCCGCUUCAAGUGGCCCUUGCUCUUCUCCAGGUUUUAUGAAGCCUACAAAUUCUCAGGCCCCAGUCUCCCCAAGAACGACGUCAUCGUGGCCGUCAACUGGACGGGUGUGUACUUUGUGGAUGAGCAGGAGCAGGUACUUCUGGAGCUGUCCUUCCCAGAGAUCAUGGCCGUGUCCAGCAGCAGGGAGUGCCGUGUCUGGCUCUCACUGGGCUGCUCUGAUCUUGGCUGUGCUGCGCCUCACUCAGGCUGGGCAGGACUGACCCCGGCGGGGCCCUGUUCUCCGUGUUGGUCCUGCAGGGGAGCGAAAACGACGGCCCCCAGCUUCACGCUGGCCACCAUCAAGGGGGACGAAUACACCUUCACCUCCAGCAAUGCUGAGGACAUUCGUGACCUGGUGGUCACCUUCCUAGAGGGGCUCCGGAAGAGAUCUAAGUAUGUUGUGGCCCUGCAGGAUAACCCCAACCCCGCAGGCGAGGAGUCAGGCUUCCUCAGCUUUGCCAAGGGAGACCUCAUCAUCCUGGACCAUGACACGGGCGAGCAGGUCAUGAACUCGGGCUGGGCCAACGGCAUCAAUGAGAGGACCAAGCAGCGUGGGGACUUCCCCACCGACAGUGUGUACGUCAUGCCCACUGUCACCAUGCCACCGCGGGAGAUUGUGGCCCUGGUCACCAUGACUCCCGAUCAGAGGCAGGACGUUGUCCGGCUCUUGCAGCUGCGAACGGCGGAGCCCGAGGUGCGUGCCAAGCCCUACACGCUGGAGGAGUUUUCCUAUGACUACUUCAGGCCCCCACCCAAGCACACGCUGAGCCGUGUCAUGGUGUCCAAGGCCCGAGGCAAGGACCGGCUGUGGAGCCACACGCGGGAACCGCUCAAGCAGGCGCUGCUCAAGAAGCUCCUGGGCAGUGAGGAGCUCUCGCAGGAGGCCUGCCUGGCCUUCAUUGCUGUGCUCAAGUACAUGGGCGACUACCCGUCCAAGAGGACACGCUCCGUCAACGAGCUCACCGACCAGAUCUUUGAGGGUCCCCUGAAAGCCGAGCCCCUGAAGGACGAGGCAUAUGUGCAGAUCCUGAAGCAGCUGACCGACAACCACAUCAGGUACAGCGAGGAGCGGGGUUGGGAGCUGCUCUGGCUGUGCACGGGCCUUUUCCCACCCAGCAACAUCCUCCUGCCCCACGUGCAGCGCUUCCUGCAGUCCCGAAAGCACUGCCCACUCGCCAUCGACUGCCUGCAACGGCUCCAGAAAGCCCUGAGAAACGGGUCCCGGAAGUACCCUCCGCACCUGGUGGAGGUGGAGGCCAUCCAGCACAAGACCACCCAGAUUUUCCACAAAGUCUACUUCCCUGAUGACACUGACGAGGCCUUCGAAGUGGAGUCCAGCACCAAGGCCAAGGACUUCUGCCAGAACAUCGCCACCAGGCUGCUCCUCAAGUCCUCAGAGGGAUUCAGCCUCUUUGUCAAAAUUGCAGACAAGGUCCUCAGCGUUCCUGAGAAUGACUUCUUCUUUGACUUUGUUCGACACUUGACAGACUGGAUAAAGAAAGCUCGGCCCAUCAAGGACGGAAUUGUGCCCUCACUCACCUACCAGGUGUUCUUCAUGAAGAAGCUGUGGACCACCACGGUGCCAGGGAAGGAUCCCAUGGCCGAUUCCAUCUUCCACUAUUACCAGGAGUUGCCCAAGUAUCUCCGAGGCUACCACAAGUGCACGCGGGAGGAGGUGCUGCAGCUGGGGGCGCUGAUCUACAGGGUCAAGUUCGAGGAGGACAAGUCCUACUUCCCCAGCAUCCCCAAGCUGCUGCGGGAGCUGGUGCCCCAGGACCUUAUCCGGCAGGUCUCACCUGAUGACUGGAAGCGGUCCAUCGUCGCCUACUUCAACAAGCACGCAGGGAAGUCCAAGGAGGAGGCCAAGCUGGCCUUCCUGAAGCUCAUCUUCAAGUGGCCCACCUUUGGCUCAGCCUUCUUCGAGGUGAAGCAAACUACGGAGCCAAACUUCCCUGAGAUCCUCCUAAUUGCCAUCAACAAGUAUGGGGUCAGCCUCAUCGAUCCCAAAACGAAGGAUAUCCUCACCACUCAUCCCUUCACCAAGAUCUCCAACUGGAGCAGCGGCAACACCUACUUCCACAUCACCAUUGGGAACUUGGUGCGCGGGAGCAAACUGCUCUGCGAGACGUCACUGGGCUACAAGAUGGAUGACCUCCUGACUUCCUACAUUAGCCAGAUGCUCACAGCCAUGAGCAAACAGCGGGGCUCCAGGAGCGGCAAGUGAACAGUCACGGGGAGGUGCUGGUUCCAUGCCUGCUCUCGAGGCAGCAGUGGGUUCAGGCCCAUCAGCUACCCCUGCAGCUGGGGAAGACUUAUGCCAUCCCGGCAGCGAGGCUGGGCUGGCCAGCCACCACUGACUAUACCAACUGGGCCUCUGAUGUUCUUCCAGUGAGGCAUCUCUCUGGGAUGCAGAACUUCCCUCCAUCCACCCCUCUGGCACCUGGGUUGGUCUAAUCCUAGUUUGCUGUGGCCUUCCCGGUUGUGAGAGCCUGUGAUCCUUAGAUGUGUCUCCUGUUUCAGACCAGCCCCACCAUGCAACUUCCUUUGACUUUCUGUGUACCACUGGGAUAGAGGAAUCAAGAGGACAAUCUAGCUCUCCAUACUUUGAACAACCAAAUGUGCAUUGAAUACUCUGAAACCGAAGGGACUGGAUCUGCAGGUGGGAUGAGGGAGACAGACCACUUUUCUAUAUUGCAGUGUGAAUGCUGGGCCCCUGCUCAAGUCUACCCUGAUCACCUCAGGGCAUAAAGCAUGUUUCAUUCUCUGGCC